UGGACAGGCCUGAGAAUCAGAGAAACCUUCUCUGGGGCUGCAAGGACCUGAGCUCAGCUUCCGCCCCAGCCAGGGAAGCGGCAGGGGAAAGCACCGGCUCCAGGCCAGCGUGGGCCGCUCUCUCGCUCGGUGCCCGCCGCCAUGUGGGCCGUCCUGAGGUUAGCCCUGCGGCCGUGUGCCCGCGCCUCUCCCGCCGGGCCGCGCGCCUAUCACGGGGACUCGGUGGCCUCGCUGGGCACCCAGCCGGACUUGGGCUCUGCCCUCUACCAGGAGAACUACAAGCAGAUGAAAGCACUAGUAAAUCAGCUCCAUGAACGAGUGGAGCAUAUAAAACUAGGAGGUGGUGAGAAAGCCCGAGCACUUCACAUAUCAAGAGGAAAACUAUUGCCCAGAGAAAGAAUUGACAAUCUCAUAGACCCAGGGUCUCCAUUUCUGGAAUUAUCCCAGUUUGCAGGUUACCAGUUAUAUGACAAUGAGGAGGUGCCAGGAGGUGGCAUUAUUACAGGCAUUGGAAGAGUAUCAGGAGUAGAAUGCAUGAUUAUUGCCAAUGAUGCCACCGUCAAAGGAGGUGCCUACUACCCAGUGACUGUGAAAAAACAAUUACGGGCCCAAGAAAUUGCCAUGCAAAACAGGCUCCCCUGCAUCUACUUAGUUGAUUCGGGAGGAGCAUACUUACCUCGACAAGCAGAUGUGUUUCCAGAUCGAGACCACUUUGGCCGUACAUUCUAUAAUCAGGCAAUUAUGUCUUCUAAAAAUAUUGCACAGGUAAUUUUUCAUGAAUAAAGUGUACAGUGGUGCUUUUUACUCUUAAGUAUCUUUACGAAUUAGGUACUCUGGGAUGGCUUGAAAGUAAAACAGAAUUUAACACAAAAUCUAAUCUUUUUUUUUUUUUUAUACUUUAGGUUUUAGGGUACAUGUGCACAUUGUGCAGGUUAGUUACAUACGUACACAUGUGCCAUGCUGGUGCGCUGCACCCACUAAAUCGUCAUCUAGCAUUAGGUAUAUCUCCCAAUGCUAUCCCUCCCCGCUCCCCCCACCCCACCACAGUCCCCAGAGUGUGAUAUUCCCCUUCCUGUGUCCAUGUGAUCUCAUUGUUCAAUUCCCACCUAUGAGUGAGAAUAUGCGGUGUUUGGUUUUUUGUUCUUGCGAUAGUUUACUGAGAAUGAUGAUUUCCAAUUUCAUCCAUGUCCCUACAAAGGACAUGAACUCAUCAUUUUUUAUGGCUGCAUAGUAUUCCAUGGUGUAUAUGUGCCACAUUUUCUUAAUCCAGUCUAUCAUUUUUGGACAUUUGGGUUGGUUCCAAGUCUUUGCUAUUGUGAAUAAUGCCGCAAUAAACAUACGUGUGCAUGUGUCUUUAUAGCAGCAUGAUUUAUAGUCCUUUGGGUAUAUACCCAGUAAUGGGAUGGCUAGGUCAAAUGGUAUUUCUAGUUCUAGAUCCCUGAGGAAUCGCCACACUGACUUCGACAAUGGUUGAACUAGUUUACAGUCCCACCAACAGUGUAAAAGUGUUCCUAUUUCUCCAUAUCCUCUCCAGCCCCUGUUGUUUCCUGACUUUUUAAUGAUUGCCAUUCUAACUGGUGUGAGAUGGUAUCUCAUUGUGGUUUUGAUUUGCAUUUCUCUGAUGGCCAGUGAUGACGAGCAUUUUUUCAUGUGUUUUUUGGCUGCAUAAAUGUCUUCUUCUGAGAAGUGUCUGUUCAUGUCCUUCACCCACUUUUUGAUGGGGUUGUUUGUUUUUUUCUUGUAAAUUUGAGUUCAUUGUAGAUUCUGGAUAUUAGCCCUUUGUCAGAUGAGUAGGUUGUGAAAAUUUUCUCCCAUUUUGUAGGUUGCCUGUUCACUCUGAUGGUAGUUUCUUUUGCUGUGCAGAAGCUCUUUAGUUUAAUUAGAUCCCAUUUGUCAAUUUUGGCUUUUGUUGCCAUUGCUUUUGGUGUUUCGGACAUGAAGUCCUUGCCCAUGCCUAUGUCCUGAAUGGUAAUGCCUAGGUUUUCUUCUAGGGUUUUUAUGGUUUUUGGUCUAAUGUUUAAGUCUUUAAUCCAUCUUGAAUUGAUUUUUGUAUAAGGUGUAAGGAAGGGAUCCAGUUUCAGCUUUCUACAUAUGGCUAGCCAGUUUUCCCAACACCAUUUAUUAAAUAGGGAAUCCUUUCCCCAUUGCUUGUUUUUCUCAGGUUUGUCAAAGAUAAGAUGUAGGUAUGCGGCGUUAUUUCUGAGGGCUCUGUUCUGUUCCAUUGAUCUAUAUCUCUGUUUUGGUACCAAUACCAUGCUGUUUUGGUUACUGUAGCCUUGUAGUACAGUUUGAAGUCAGGUAGUGUGAUGCCUCCAGCUUUGUUCUUUUGGCUUAGGAUUGCCUUGGCGAUGUGGGCUCUUUUUUGGUUCCAUGUGAACUUUAAAGUAGUUUUUUCCAAUUCUGUGAAGAAAGUCUUUGGUAGCUUGAUGGGGAUGGCAUUGAAUCUGUAAAUUACCUUGGGCAGUAUGGCCAUUUUCACGAUAUUGAUUCUUCCUACCCAUGAGCAUGGAAUGUUCUUCCAUUUGUUUGUAUCCUCUUUUAUUUCCUUGAGCAGUGGUUUGUAGUUCUCCUUGAAGAGGUCCUUCACAUCCCUUGUAAGUUGGAUUCCUAGGUAUUUUAUUCUCUUUGAAGCAAUUGUGAAUGAGAGUUCACUCAUGAUUUGGCUCUCUGUUUGUCUGUUGUUGGUAUUUAAGAAUGCUUGUGAUUUUUGUACAUUGAUUUUGUAUCCUGAGACUUUGCUGAAGUUGCUUAUCAGCUUGAGGAGAUUUUGGGCUGAGACAAUGGGGUUUUCUAGAUAUACAAUCAUGUCGUCUGCAAACAGGGACAAUUUGACUUCCUCUUUUCCUAAUUGAAUACCCUUUAUUUCCUUCUCCUGCCUAAUUGCCCUGGCCAGAACUUCCAACACUAUGUUGAAUAGGAGUGGUGAGAGAGGGCAUCCCUGUCUUGUGCCAGUUUUCAAAGGGAAUGCUUCCAGUUUUUGCCCAUUCAGUAUGAUAUUGGCUGUGGGUUUGUCAUAGAUAGCUCUUAUUAUUUUGAAAUACGUCCCAUCAAUACCUAAUUUAUUGAGAGUUUUUAGCAUGAAGGGUUGUUGAAUUUUGUCAAAGGCUUUUUCUGCAUCUAUUGAGAUAAUCAUGUGGUUUUUGUCUUUGGCUCUGUUUAUAUGCUGGAUUACAUUUACUGAUUUGCAUAUAUUGAACCAGCCUUGCAUCCCAGGGAUGAAGCCCACUUGAUCAUGGUGGAUAAGCUUUUUGAUGUGCUGCUGGAUGCGUUUUGCCAGUAUUUUAUUGAGGAUUUUUGCAUCAAUGUUCAUCAAGGAUAUUGGUCUAAAAUUCUCUUUUUUGGUUGUGUCUCUGCCCGGCUUUGGUAUCAGAAUGAUGCUGGCCUCAUAAAAUGAGUUAGGGAGGAUUCCCUCUUUUUCUACUGAUUGGAAUAGUUUCAGAAGGAAUGGUACCAGUUCCUUCUUGUACCUCUGGUAGAAUUCGGCUGUGAAUCCAUCUGGUCCUGGACUCUUUUUGGUUGGUAAACUAUUGAUUAUUGCCACAAUUUCAGCUCCUGUUAUUGGUCUAUUCAGAGAUUCAACUUCUUCCUGGUUUAGUCUUGGGAGAGUUUGUGUGUCGAGGAAUUUAUCCAUUUCUUCUAGAUUUUCUAGUUUAUUUGCGUAGAGGUGUUUGUAGUAUUCUCUGAUGGUAGUUUGUAUUUCUGUGGGAUCGGUGGUGAUAUCCCCUUUAUCAUUUUUUAUUGCGUCUAUUUGAUUCUUCUCUCUUUUUUUCUUUAUUAGUCUUGCUAGCGGUCUAUCAAUUUUGUUGAUCCUUUCAAAAAACCAGCUCCUGGAUUCAUUAAUUUUUUGAAGGGUUUUUUGUGUCUCUAUUUCCUUCAGUUCUGCUCUGAUUUUAGUUAUUUCUUGCCUUCUGCUAGCUUUUGAACGUGUUUGCUCUUGCUUUUCUAGUUCUUUUAAUUGUGAUGUUAGGGUGUCAAUUUUGGAUCUUUCCUGCUUUCUCUUGUGGGCAUUUAGUGCUAUAAAUUUCCCUCUACACACUGUUUGAAUGCGUCCCAGAGAUUCUGGUAUGUUGUGUCUUUGUUCUUGUUGGUUUCAAAGAACAUCUUUAUUUCUGCCUUCAUUUCGUUAUGUACCCAGUGGUCAUUCAGGAGCAGGUUGUUCAGUUUCCAUGUAGUUGAGCAGUUUUGAGUGAGAUUCUUAAUCCUGAGUUCUAGUUUGAUUGCACUGUGGUCUGAGAGAUAGUUUAUUAUAAUCUCUGUUCUUUUACAUUUGCUGAGGAGAGCUUUACUUCCAAGUAUGUGGUCAAUUUUGGAAUAGGUGUGGUGUGGUGCUGAAAAAAAUGUAUAUUCUGUUGAUUUGGGGUGGAGAGUUCUGUAGAUGUCUAUUAGGUCCGCUUGGUGCAGAGCUGAGUUCAAUUCCUGGGUAUCCUUGUUGACUUUCUGUCUCGUUGAUCUGUCUAAUGUUGACAGUGGGGUGUUAAAGUCUCCCAUUAUUAAUGUGUGGGAGUCUAAGUCUCUUUGUAGGUCACUCAGGACUUGCUUUAUGACUCUGGGUGCUCCUGUAUUGGGUGCAUAUAUAUUUAGGAUAGUUAGCUCUUCUUGUUGAAUUGAUCCCUUUACCAUUAUGUAAUGGCCUUCUUUGUCUCUUUUGAUCUUUGUUGGUUUAAAGUCUGUUUUAUCAGAGACUAGGAUUGCAACCCCUGCCUUUUUUUGUUUUCCAUUUGCUUGGUAGAUCUUCCUCCAUCCUUUUAUUUUGAGCCUAUGUGUGUCUCUGCACGUGAGAUGGGUUUCCUGAAUACAGCACACUGAUGGGUCUUGACUCUUUAUCCAGUUUGCCAGUCUGUGUCUUUUAAUUGGAGCAUUUAGUCCAUUUACAUUUAAAGUUAAUAUUGUUAUGUGUGAAUUUGAUCCUGUCAUUAUGAUGUUAGCUGGUGAUUUUGCUUGCUAGUUGAUGCAGUUUCUUCCUAGUCUUGAAGGUCUUUACAUUUUGGCUUGAUUUUUGCAGUGGCUGGUACCGGUUGUUCCUUUCCAUGUUUAGCGCUUCCUUUUUUAGGGCAGGCCUGGUGGUGACAGAAUCUCUCAGCAUUUGCUUGUCUGUAAAGGAUUUUAUUUCUCCUUCACUUAUGAAGCUUAGUUUGGCUGGAUAUGAAAUUCUGGGUUGCAAAUUCUUUUCUUUAAGAAUGUUGAAUAUUGGCCCCUAGUCUCUUCUGGCUUGUAGGUUUCUGCCGAGAGAUCCGCUGUUAGUCUGAUGGGCUUCCCUUUGAGGGUAACCCGACCUUUCUCUCUGGCUGCCCUUAACAUUUUUUCCUUCAUUUCAACUUUGGUGAAUCUGACAAUUAUGUGUCUUGGAGUUGCUCUUCUCGAGGAGUAUCUUUGUGGUGUUCUGUGUAUUUCCUGAAUCUGAACGUUGGCCUGCCUUGCUAGAUUGUGGAAGUUCUCCUGGAUAAUAUCCUGCAGAGUGUUUUCCAACUUGGUUCCAUUCUCCCCAUCACUUUCAGGUACACCAAUCAGACGUAGAUUUGGUCUUUUCACAUAGUCCCAUAUUUCUUGGAGGCUUUGCUCAUUUCUUUUUAUUCUUUUUUCUCUAAACUUCCCUUCUCGCUUCAUUUCAUUCAUUUCAUCUUCCAUUGCUGAUACCCUUUCUUACAGUUGAUCGCUUCAGCUCCUGAGGCUUCUGCAUUCUUCACGUAGUUCUCGAGCCUUGGUUUUCAGCUCCAUCAGCUCCUUUAAGCACUUCUCUGUAUUGGUUAUUCUAGUUAUACAUUCUUCUAAAUUUUUUUCAAAGUUUUCAACUUCUUUGCCUUUAGUUUGAAUGUCCUCCCGUAGCUCAGAGUAAUUUGAUCGUCUGAAGCCUUCUUCUCUCAGCUCAUCAAAGUCAUUCCCCAUCCAGCUUUGUUCCGUUGCUGGUGAGGAACUGCGUUCCUUUGGAGGAGGAGAGGUGCUCUGCGUUUUAGAGUUUCCAGUUUUUCUGUUCUGUUUUUUCCCCAUCUUUGUGGUUUUAUCUACUUUUGGUCUUUGAUGAUAGUGAUGUACAGAUGGGUUUUUGGUGUGGAUGUCCUUUCUGUUUGUUAGUUUUCCUUCUAACAGACAGGACCCUCAGCUGCAGGUCUGUUGGAAUACCCUGCCGUGUGAGAUGUCAGUGUGCCCCUGCUGGGGGGUGCCUCCCAGUUAGGCUGCUCGGGGGUCAGGGGUCAGGGACCCACUUGAGGAGGCAGUCUGCCCGUUCUCAGAUCUCCAGCUGUGUGCUGGGAGAACCACUGCUCUCUUCAAAGCUGUCAGACAGGGACAUUUAAGUCUGCAGAGGUUACUGCUGUCUUUUUGUUUGUCUGUGCCCUGCCCCCAGAGGGGAGCCUACAGAGGCAGGCAGGCCUCCUUGAGCUGUGGUGGGCUCCACCCAGUUCGAGCUUCCUGGCUGCUUUGUUUACCUUAAGCAAGCCUGGGCAAUGGCGAGCGCCCCUCCCCCAGCCUCGCUGCCGCCUUGCAGUUUGAUCUCAGACUGCUGUGCUAGCAAUCAGCGAGACUCCGUGGGCGUAGGACCCUCCGAGCCAGGUGCGGGAUAUAAUCUCCUGGUGCGCCGUUUUUUAAGCUGGUCCGAAAAGCGCAAUAUUCGGGUGGGAGUGACCCGAUUUUCCAGGUGCGUCCGUCACCCCUUUCUUUGACUCGGAAAGGGAACUCCCUGACCCCUUGCGCUUCCCAAGUGAGGCAAUGCCUCGCCCUGCUUCGGCUCGCACACGGUGCGCGCACCCACUGACCUGCGCCCACUGUCUGGCACUCCUUAGUGAGAUGAACCCAGUACCUCAGAUGGAAAUGCAGAAAUCACCCGUCUUCUGCGUCGCUCACGCUGAGAGCUGUAGACCGGAGCUGUUCCUAUUCGGCCAUCUUGGCUCCUCCCCAAAAUCUAAUCUUUUUCCACAGAGAGUAUCUAAAGGUUGUCUCCAAUUAGAGCUUUUUAUUAACUAUAGGAAUACUCCUAUACUGUAAUAAGAUUAUUAAAACAGGUUUUAGGCCAGGCGCGGUGGCUCACGCCUGGAAUCCCAGCACUUUGGGAGGCCGAGGUGGGGGGAUCACGAGGUCAGGAGAUCGAGACUAUCCUGGCUAACGCGGUGAAACCCCGUCUCUAUUAAAAAUACAAAAAAUUAGCUGGGCGUGGUGGCACAUGCCUGUAGUCCCAGCAACUUGGGAGACUGAGGCAGGAGAAAUGCUUGAACCUGGGAGGCAGAGGUUGCAGUGAGCUGAGAUCAUGCCACUGCACUCCAGCCUGGCGACGAAGUGAGACUCCGUCUCAAACAAACAAAGAACAGGUUUUUAAAAGGAAAACAGGGUUUAAAAAGAAAGGGCUCCAGUAAUUCCUUUUUUAGGGCUAUACCCUAGGGAAACUCUGAUAUAUGUAUGAAGAGAUACUUAGAAGAAUAAUUCAUGGCCAGGCACUGUGACUUGUGCCUGAAAUCCCAGCACUUUGGGAGGCUGAAGUGAGAGGAUCACUUGAGUCCAGGAGUGAGAGACCAGCCUGGGCAACAUAGGGAGACCCUGUCUCUACAAAAAAAUAAAAAA